GGGCUCUCCUGACGCGGCCGGGCCGGACCCCGGAGGAACCAGCUGGCCAGCUGGCAAGGGGCUGGCUGCAGUUCCGACAGCGGCGGUGCCGGGAGGGGUAGGUGAGGGUCGCGAGGCGGCCCUGAGCUUCUGAGUGAGCGUGGUGCUUUUGGGAACUCGGGACGGGCGACCCGUGGAGCCAGGAGCGGGGCCGAGGCGCUGAGACGCGGCGGCGCGGCUGCCGGCUGGAUGGGAAGUUAAUGUUUACGGCGAAGUCUACUCAACGUUUCCAAGGUGAGGGGCGCUGCGCCAGGCCGGGCGGGCCGGGAGGCCGGGCGGGCGGUGAGUCCGUGUUCCGCUGGCGCACAGCUGGGCCGAGGCGCGGCGGGCGGGGGCCGCCGCAAGUUUUGCUGUGGGAGCGGGGCGGGCGCGCCUGGCCCCGCCAGGGCCUAAGUUCCCUGCACUCGCUUCCUCGCCUGUCGCCGCCGCCGCCGCCCGCAGCCCUCCUUCUCGUGGGCGCUGGGGAAGAAACUCGUCGGCGGGUCUAACUGUGGCGUCCCAGGGCGGUGGAGGGACGGAGCAGCUUCGGGGGCACGUCCUCGUAAAUCCCGUGGAGGACACUGACCCUGCACCCCACCCUCGAGGCCAGAAGUCGGUUCCCUUUGGGGACCUGAGGGGCGAGAGCACUCGCCCCCCUGACUUGCAAAGUUGGCGUCUUUACUUGGCCUCCGGGAUUCUGCGCAUGGCGUGUCUCCAGGCUGCUGAUGGGCAAGACAGAUGUGCCAGGUCCAGAAUGAACUUGAGAAGAGUUUGUAGCCAUUCCUGAAUCACCUUAUGACUAGUGGGGCAAGCCUCAAAUUAACCUCAGGAUUUCCGGUGGCGACAGACAAAGUUGCAGAAAAGCUGAGCUCUACUCUCUCAUGGGUGAAGAACACAGUAUCGCAUACAGUCAGUCAGAUGGCCAGUCAGGUGGCAAGUCCAUCUACUUCAUUACAUACCACAUCCUCAUCUACCACACUAUCAACACCAGCCCUUUCACCAUCUUCCCCAUCACAGUUGAGUCCAGACGACUUAGAACUCCUGGCUAAACUGGAAGAACAGAAUAGAUUGUUAGAAACGGAUAGUAAGUCUUUAAGAUCUGUAAAUGGGUCAAGAAGAAACAGUGGCUCUUCUCUUGUGUCGAGUUCAUCAGCCUCUAGCAACCUCAGUCACCUUGAAGAAGAUUCUUGGAUUCUUUGGGGAAGAAUUGUUAAUGAAUGGGAAGAUGUACGCAAAAAGAAGGAAAAGCAAGUUAAGGAACUUGUUCAUAAAGGGAUACCCCAUCACUUUAGAGCAAUAGUUUGGCAACUUUUAUGCAGUGCACAAAGUAUGCCAAUUAAGGAUCAGUAUUCAGAACUCCUGAAAAUGACCUCGCCUUGUGAAAAAUUGAUCCGAAGGGACAUUGCUAGAACUUACCCUGAACACAACUUUUUUAAGGAAAAAGAUAGCCUUGGACAGGAGGUUUUAUUUAAUGUAAUGAAGGCUUACUCUUUAGUAGAUCGUGAGGUUGGUUACUGUCAAGGAAGUGCUUUUAUAGUUGGAUUGUUGCUUAUGCAGAUGCCAGAAGAAGAAGCUUUCUGUGUAUUUGUUAAAUUAAUGCAAGAUUAUAGACUUCGUGAACUUUUUAAACCAAGUAUGGCAGAAUUGGGCCUUUGUAUGUACCAGUUUGAAUGUAUGAUACAGGAGCAUCUUCCAGAGCUCUUUGUACAUUUUCAAUCUCAGAGUUUUCAUACCUCAAUGUAUGCAUCAUCCUGGUUUCUGACUAUCUUUCUUACAACUUUUCCACUACCAAUUGCAACAAGGAUAUUUGAUAUCUUUAUGUCUGAGGGUUUAGAAAUAGUGUUUCGUGUAGGAUUAGCACUUCUUCAGAUGAAUCAGGCAGAACUGAUGCAACUUGACAUGGAAGGGAUGUUACAGCACUUUCAAAAGGUCAUUCCACAUCAGUUUGAUGGUGUCCCAGACAAGCUAAUCCAAGCAGCUUACCAAGUCAAAUACAAUUCAAAAAAAAUGAAAAAGCUUGAAAAGGAAUACACUACAAUAAAAACGAAAGAAAUGGAAGAGCAAGUUGAAAUUAAAAGGUUACGCACAGAAAAUAGACUUUUAAAACAGCGCAUCGAGACAUUAGAAAAAGAAAGUGCUUCCUUGGCAGAUAGAUUGAUACAGCAUAAAUGCAGUUCCAACUACAACGAAGAUUUUGUGCUACAGCUAGAGAAGGAAUUGGUCCAAGCCCGACUGAGUGAAGCUGAGUCUCAGUGUGCAUUAAAAGAGAUGCAGGAUAAAGUCUUGGAUAUAGAGAAGAGGAAUAACUCCCUUCCUGAUGAGAAUAAUAUUGCAAGGCUUCAGGAAGAACUCAUUGCUGUGAAACUUAGAGAAGCAGAAGCCAUUAUGGGUUUGAAAGAACUUAGACAGCAAGUCAAGGAUUUAGAGGAACACUGGCAGCGCCACUUAGCUCGUACUACUGGGAGAUGGAAAGACCCACCCAAGAAAAAUGCUAUGAAUGAGUUACAAGAUGAACUGAUGACCAUUCGACUUAGAGAAGCUGAAACACAAGCAGAAAUAAGAGAAAUAAAACAAAGGAUGAUGGAAAUGGAAACACAGAACCAGAUCAAUAGUAACCAUCUUCGAAGAGCAGAACAAGAGGUGAUUAGCCUACAGGAGAAAGUGCAGUAUCUUUCUGCACAGAACAAAGGACUCCUUACUCAAUUAAGUGAAGCAAAGCGUAAACAAGCAGAGAUUGAAUGCAAGAAUAAGGAAGAAGUGAUGGCUGUGAGGCUUCGGGAAGCAGAUAGCAUAGCUGCUGUGGCUGAACUACGACAACACAUUGCUGAGCUUGAAAUCCAGAAAGAAGAAGGAAAGCUUCAAGGACAGCUUAACAAGUCUGAUUCUAACCAGUAUAUUGGGGAACUGAAAGAUCAGAUAGCAGAGCUGAAUCAUGAGCUCAGGUGCCUAAAAGGCCAGAGGGGCUUCUCAGGCCAACCUCCUUUUGAUGGAAUCCACAUUGUCAACCAUUUAAUAGGAGAUGAUGAAUCAUUCCAUUCCUCCGAUGAAGAUUUUAUAGAUAAUUCCUUACAGGAAACUGGUGUUGGUUUUCCUUUGCACGGAAAAUCUGGUUCGAUGUCUUUGGACCCCGCAGUGGCAGAUGGUAGUGAGAGCGAAACAGAAGACAGUGUGCUGGAGACCAGAGAGAGCAACCAAGUGGUUCAAAAGGAGCGGCCCCCGAGAAGAAGAGAGUCGUAUUCAACCACUGUCUGACCAUCACUGUGACCUAGACUAUGGAUUUAUUUAAGGGAUCAGUUAUCAUAUGAUUAGGGCUUUUUGGAAAUAAUUUGUUUCAUAUGUACAUAUAUAUAUAUAUAUAUAUAUAUAUAUAUAUAUAUAUAUAUAUAUAUAUAUAUAUUUUACAGUCUUAUCUGCCUUUUUAUCUUUGCCAAAUCUUUACCACUGAUUUACCAUUGCCAUAAAGUAGACUGGUAUAUGGUUAAUGUGUAAAACAAGGUUCUAACAGUAUUACUGAAUAUUAAUGUUUCUUGUUUAGAAAAUGCAACUAUAUCUAUAUGUGGGAACCAUUCUGAAGUUCAAAACUAUGGAAAAUUGAAUUUUCUUCAGACAAAACUGCUCUUGUGCAAUAUUUUAUGCUCAGUGAGCAAAUUGUGUAUUUAUGUUUAUCAAUUUGUUCUCAAGGUGGCUGUCUACAGACAUUUGACCAAGACAUACAUCUGAUUUACCUUGUGUUUUUUUUUUUAUUGUUGUUUUUUUUUUUAAGACAGAGAUUCAGUCUGUCACCCAGGCUGGAGUGCUGUGGUGUGAUCUUAGCUCACUGCAACCUCCGCCUCCCAGGUUCAAGCAAUUUUCCUGCCUCAGCCUCCCGAGUACCUGGGACUAUAUGUGCGCACCACCACGCCUGGCUAAUUUUUUGUAUUUUUAGUAGAGAUGGGGUUUCACCAUGUUGGCUGGGCUGGUCUCGAACUCCUAACCUCAAGUGAUCCACCCGCCUCAGCCUCCCAAAGUGCUGGGAUUACAGGUGUGAGCCACUGCACCCAGCCUACCUUGUCUGUUUGUGUCUGGGAGGUUUUUUUUUUCUAUUUUUAUUUUUUCAUGAAAAUUAUUGGUGGGCCACUGAAAGUCCCCACACACAAAGCCUUUAUUCUAUAUAAUUUUAUAAACACAAAUUCAUGAUUAUCUGUUUUGAGAGUUUUAAGUUUUGUUUUAAUGUUUAACUUUUAUGUGCAUAUGAUGCUUCCAUGUGUUGGUUACUAGAGUAGUAGGUUAACUACAGACAUACUGUUUUGUUUGUACAUAUUUAUAAAUCUGUACCACCUAACAUUGAACAUCAUUUUAUAUGAAGAACAUACAUGUUGCAAAAUGACUGCUUUCAGCAUCUAACAGGACUUCUGUAAAUAAUAGGUUAAAAGUUAAAAAUAAAACACUAAUGUUUUAAGAGCUUUAGUAUUUUGCUUAGCAUUCAAUACUAGCAGAUUCAUAACUGAUGCCUGUUCAAAAACACUGUUGGUGGAAUCUUUUAUUUCAUGUGUAUGUAACUACUAAAUUUUUCAUGACUGAAGAGGUUAUAGCACAUAUUAGUUAGUGCUAAUAUUCUACUGAAUAUAAUUUAAGCAAUGGGCUAAGGUCCAAGAAACAUAGCAAUUAUAUCUACAAAUAAUCUAUUAACAUGAUCUUCAGAAUCUCUAGUUUUUGUUCUAUAGAUAAAGCCAUAAGAAUCCUUUCCUACCAGUUUUUCCUAUAUCAUUUAGAUAUUAUUUCCUAGAAAACAGGAUGCCUGUCACUGAUAAGUUAGAGAAAACACCCAAAUUAUACUUGCACUAUGGAAAGACGACAUGAAUAUGUUGACUGGGUACUUUCUACUCUCAUUUUUGUUAGCCUAUGAAAAAAAAAACAUUUUGUUAACCUAUGGAAAAAGCCUUGGAAGAGAAAAGUAGAAUUCAGUAUGUAUGGAGGCACAGUUUUGCACAGUAUGUUGCAUGCGGCAAAAAAAAAAAUAUGAAAUAGAGUAGAAGAGAUAAAAGUAGUUUUCUGUCAAAAACUAGGAGUUAAGCCUUCAGGUACGUUGUGGACUAGGCUUUCCAGCAAGGUUUUUGUAGCUAUUUGCUUGCCUGAGAAAUGAAAUUGAAAACAUACCCCUGCGUGUCUGUCCUUAACACCAGGCUAAAUUCUGGUGGUUAAAUAACUUAUCUGUGGUUACAAGCUAGUAAGUAGCAGAGCCAAGAUUUUUUUUAAUAUAGAGACAGGUGUCUCACUGUGUUGUCCAGGCUGGUCUUGAACUCCUGGCCUCAAGUGGUCCUCCUGCCUCAGCCUCCCAAAGUGUGGGGAUUACAGGUGCGAGCUACUGCUCCCAGCAAGAGCCAAGAUUUUAACCUAGAUCUCCCUAACACCAAAGCUUUUGAAAGGGUUCAGCUGAAGAAUUUCUCAAUUCUCUGUUUUGUUUUGUUUUUAUUUUUGUUUUUUGAGAUGAAGUCUCACUGCACUCAGGCUGGAGUGCAGUGGUACGAUCUUGGCUCACUGCAACCUCCACCUCCCGGGUUCAAGCGAUUCUCCUGCCUCAGCUCCCAAGUAGCUGGGACUACAGGUGCACGCCACCACAACUGGCUAAUUUUUGUAUUUUUAGUAGAGAUGGGGUUUCGCUAUGUUGGCCAGGCUGAUCUCAAACUUCUGACCUCAGGUGAUCCACCCACUUUGACCUCCCAAAGUGCUGGGAUUACUAGACGUAAGCCACCACACCUGGCAAUUCCCUGCUUUUUUGACAACAUAAUUUAAAUGAAUUUGAUUUAAAUGUUUCCUGAAUAUAUAUACAGAUAGAUAGAUGAGUAUCAACACUUACAAGCUCUACACAGUCUGUGAGUGUAGAUACUACUUACUCGUAGGAUUGUCUUGUGCUUUGGGGAUUUUUGUUCGGAGUUCUAUACUAUCAGCCCAGAAAGCUAUCAAUGUCCAAGUGAAGUGAGAUGAUGCAUGGCCACAUUAUUGCUUUGACCCUCACAUCAAGAAAUCUGAAUGAUCUGGACCAGGGGUCAGCAAAGUGCAGCCUACAAGCUAUUGCAGUCAGCUGCCAGUUUUUACUUUUUUAAAUAGUUGGGAAAAAAAUUCCAAAGACUGAUAUUUUGUGUCACAUGAAAAUUAUAUGAAAUUCAAAUUGCAGUGUCCAUAAGUAAAGUUUUAUUGGGGCACACCCAUGCUCACCCUUUUAAAUAUUGUGUAUGGCCGCUUUGUGCUACAGUAGCAGAGUUGAGUCAUUGCAAGGGAGACCAUAUGGCCCAGGUAGCCUAAAAUAUUUAUCUGAUCCUUUACAGAAAAAGUUUGCUAACCCUUGAUAACAGAUACUCUAAAAUGCAGGUUUUUCUUCUUCAAUUUAGCUCAGUGGUAGGUCAAAUUGUUUGCUUUUGCUAUUAAGCUUAUGAUUUGGAAACGUAAAAUUUCAUGGUGGAUAUUAUAAUCAGAACUAUUCAAAAGGGAAAACAUGCCAGCCAUUUUAUAUGAUGAAGUCUCUUAUUCCAUAGAAAACUGUAGAAAGAUAUCUGUAUCUUUGGAGAAGGAGAAAGAAAGGAAAGAACUCCAGAAUCCCAUCACUGUUCUUUAAAGCAUGCAUCACAGACCUUUAAGAGUAUGCUUUAUUGAGUAAAGGUUAUAGUUUGACUUUAAGAUAAGAAAUUUUCUAGAAUCAUGUUUGAAUUCUAAACGUUGAUAUUCUUAAGUACCAUUUCUGAUUAGGAAUUAGGUGUUAAAAGAAUCAUGGUAAGGAAACCUUAAUCCGUUGAAACUCUUGUAAUUUGGACAACAAAAAACUAGAAAUAACACUCUUUUCUUUGAAGAUCUGAUUCAAAUACACCUUAGAAGAGUUUAAAAUCUCCCAGGCCUUUAGGAUGCAAUAGGAUAUUAUGCCUUGGUUUGACUCCUUUUCAUUCAAAUUAAUGUAAGUAUGUUGUUCAAGACUUUGAAGCAUUGAACAAUGUUCUCGAUGAAUUUUAUUUAAUUACUGACAUUUUGUGAUAUUUGAAUGUUAUUAAGUUAAACACUUAGAGUUGAGUAUAUUCAGGGGAGAAAAGUGAAUGAAAUGACUCAUAAUAAGAAAGCUUGCUCCCUUGGGACAGUUACCUUCCUGGUGUCAUUGCCAUCCUGGGUUGACAAGCUGAGAGUAGAGGAUACAAGUGAUGUGAAUAAAAUGGAAAUUGCAUUGAGUUAAUGAAACAGACACUUUUAGAUCAAGAAAACACUUCAACAGCCUUUUUAGAAAUUGGCACACUCCUAUAGUCCCACCUACUCAAGAGGCUGAGGCAGGAGGAUCACUAGAGUACAGGAGUUUGGGGCUGUAGUGUGUAAUGAUCACACCUGUGAAAGAAUAACCACUGCACUCCAACCUGGGCAACAUGGCAAGACCCUGUCUCUUUAAAAAAAAAAAAAAUCCUGGGAAAAGAAGUCAAAGAUGUAAUUUUACACAAUUUCUGCCCCCACCGUCUUUUUUGUUUGUUUGUUUGUUUGUUUGUUUUUUGGCUAGAUACUAGGUAUUCAGUGUUUGCUGAGAUGACAGGUUUCUACUAAUCAGCCAGUUAUUUGGGAAGGAGAAAAACUUUUUCUCAAUUCUGAACAUGAUGCAGCUUGUUAACUCUCCAGAUAGUGCCUUUGAUUGAAAAUAAGGUCUACACCUUUUUAAGUAUAUUAUUUCUGACAUCGUAAGAAAUAAUUUAGUUCCUUAUUCUCAUUUAUCUUUUAUAUAAUGUACUGUAAUAUUCAGGUUUAAAGUAAAAUAAGUAUAUGAAUUAUAUUUUGGUAAAACUGUUUCAUGACCAGCUUGAUUAAUGUAUAUUAACAUACCAGACAUUGACAGCGAACAUUUCAUGAAAUCAGUUAUUUACUUACCAAAACAAUGAGUUUUAGCUUGAAAGUUACUGCUGCUCUAUUAUUAACAAAACUAAGUUUUAAAAAUUAAUUUUAAUUCUACUGAAGUUUAAUUUCUGGUUAAAGGUAUAGUGGAUGCUAUUUAUGAUCCAAGUUUUUACAUCACAUCCAUUGAUCUGCCUAUCCCUUCUUUUUACUCCAAAGAGGAGAUGAUAGAAUAAUACAUUCAGUAUACUACCAAGAAGCAAAGUUAUAAUGUGUUUCAUUUUGCUAUUGGAAUUUUUUAUUGUAACAUUGUAUGAUAACCUGAAAUGUUUACUUGUGCCUUUUCUUUAAACAAUUAAAGUUUUCCAUUUUAUAAGAA